AGCAUCCCUCUGGCUCCAGAGCUCAGAGCCACCCACAGCCGCAGCCAUGCUGUGCCUCCUGCUCACCCUGGGCGUGGCCCUGGUCUGUGGUGUCCCGGCCAUGGACAUCCCCCAGACCAAGCAGGACCUGGAGCUCCCAAAGUUGGCAGGGACCUGGCACUCCAUGGCCAUGGCGACCAACAACAUCUCCCUCAUGGCGACACUGAAGGCCCCUCUGAGGGUCCACAUCACCUCACUGUUGCCCACCCCCGAGGACAACCUGGAGAUCGUUCUGCACAGAUGGGAGAACAACAGCUGUGUUGAGAAGAAGGUCCUUGGAGAGAAGACUGAGAAUCCAAAGAAGUUCAAGAUCAACUAUACGGUGGCGAACGAGGCCACGCUGCUCGAUACUGACUACGACAAUUUCCUGUUUCUCUGCCUACAGGACACCACCACCCCCAUCCAGAGCAUGAUGUGCCAGUACCUGGGCAAGGCCUCUGGAGCUCCCCAGCUCUCAUGGAAGCCCCAGGGGCCCAGGACUGACCCAGCCUCUUCCACAGCCAGAGUCCUGGUGGAGGACGAUGAGAUCAUGCAGGGAUUCAUCAGGGCUUUCAGGCCCCUGCCCAGGCACCUAUGGUACUUGCUGGACUUGAAACAGAUGGAAGAGCCGUGCCGUUUCUAGGUGAGCUCCUGCCUGGUCCUGCCUCCUGGCUCACCUCCGCCUCCAGGAAGACCAGACUCCCACCCUUCCACACCUCCAGAGCAGUGGGACUUCCUCCUGCCCUUUCAAAGAAUAACCACAGCUCAGAAGACGAUGACGUGGUCAUCUGUGUCGCCAUCCCCUUCCUGCUGCACACCUGCACCACGGCCAUGGGGAGGCUGCUCCCUGGGGGCAGAGUCUCUGGCAGAGGUUAUUAAUAAACCCUUGGAGCAUGUCCUGUCUGGAUGCGCAGCCACUGCUGGGUGUGGGAUUCAGGGACGAGGGCCUGGGGUCGGGGCAGGCCCAGGCCACCGCCUGGCAGAACCGGAGCUCCUACAGACCCAUGGGCAGCUUCUGGUGGAGAAAAUACCUCAAGUUUCUUAUCUACAAAACAAAAGGGUCCACUUUCACAAA